AACUUUCGCUGUGAGGACUCGUUGCGAGAGGCUAGAGUCGCGCAGGGGCGGCCUCGGAGCCGCCCUCUCUCACGCAGACUGCCGCGGGGACUCAGCCUUGGGGCCACCCGGAGGGGACCCACGGCCCUCCUGGCGCGCUCACGGGCUGCGGGCAGCGCUGGCCUCCGCGGCUGAUGGGGGCGGCUAGUGCCGCCCCGGGCGCAGGUGACACUCGCCCGGCCAGGGUUUCCUCUGGCUGGGGAGAGCCCCGGGAGGGCGAGACUCAGACACCUCUGGGGCGGAGGACAAGGCAGCGAUGGCCCGAGAGCUGAGCCAGGAGGCACUACUGGACUUUCUGUGCCAGGCUGGGGGCCGCGUGACCAACGCUGCCUUGCUGAGCCACUUCAAGAGCUUUCUCCGAGACCCCGACGCGUCCCCCAGCCAGCACCAGCACCGCCGCGAGCUCUUCAAGGGCUUCGUCAACUCGGUCGCCGCAGUGCGCCAGGACCCCGACGGCACCAAGUACGUGGUGCUCAAGAGGAGAUACAGGGACCUUUUGGGGGAGGAGGGGCUGCAGCGACCCCGCGAGCCGCCCGCGGCCGCCCCCAGUGCAGGGGGAGCUGCGCCCUGCUCCCCGCGAGGCGCGCGCCGGGGGGAGCCGCCCCAGCAGCAGCCCAGGCGGCGGCGGCGCGAGAAGGAGCCGGAGGAGGAGCCAGCAGGUGCAGCAGCCAGAGCCGCCGACGCAGCUUGCAAUGGACUCCCGGGCAGCGACUCCCGUAGGGCGCCCGGGAAGGGCGGCGGAUCGAAGGGCAGUCCCGGACAGAGGCCGCCGGUGCCCGCAGCUGCAGCGGCAGGGGCCCAGGCGAGAGCGAGCUGCGCGGCGGCGAAGACGCAGGGCCGCUGCUGCUGGGAAUGCCUCCAGAACAACCUGGCUGUACUGCCGGGAGAGCUCGGCGCACUCCCGCACUCGGCCACCGCGGAGGAGAAGCCGGCACGGGCUCUGCCUGCCCAGGAUGACCGCGGGGCUUCCAGGGAGCGGGAAGAAGGCGCGCUAGCUGAGCCGGCGCCUGUGCCUGCAGUGGCUCACUCGCCUCCCGCCACCGUCGAGGCUGCGACAAGCAGGGCUUCCCCGCCUGCUCUCCUGCCCGGCCCCGCUCCCCGCGGAGACCGGCCGGAGCUGCUGACCCCCAGCUCCCUGCAUUAUUCGACCCUGCAGCAGCAGCAGCAGCGCACUCGAGAGUGGGUGGCCAGGCACCCGCAGGUGCCCGAGGCCCGUGAUCAGGGCCCUAUCCGCGCCUGGUCGGUGCUGCCAGACAACUUCCUCCAGCUGCCCUUGGAACCCGGCUCCACGGAGCCUAAUUCAGAGCCGCCAGACCCCUGUCUUUCCUCGCACUCUCUCUUUCCUGUUGUUCCGGAUGAGUCCUGGGAAUCCUGGGCGGGGAACCCUUCAUUGACUGUCUUUCGCAGCAUUCGUUGUCAGCUGUCCCUCCAAGAUCUGGAUGACUUUGUGGACCAGGAGAGUGAUGGCAGUGAGGAGAGCAGCAGUGGGCCCAAAGACUCCCCGGGGGCUUCUGAAGAGGGGCUGCAGGUUGUCUUGGGAACCCCAGAUAGGGGGAAGCUCAGGAAUCCAGCUGGGGGCCUUUCUGUAUCUCGGAAGGAGGGCAGCCCCAGCCGGAGCCCUCAGGGUCUCAGAAACAGAGGGGAUGGUCACAUCUCUCAGCAGGUCCCUGCAGGGGCUAAUGGCCUUGCAGGCCACCCCCUGAAGCCUUUGCCUUGGCCAGUUCCUAAGUUAAGGAGGUCCCUCAGGAGGAGCUCUCUGGCAGGGAGAGCCAAAUUGUCCUCCUCUGAUGAGGAGUACCUCGAUGAGGGCUUGCUGAAAAGAAGUCGGCGCCCACCUCGAUCCAGGAAGCCCUCCAAGGCAGGAACGGCACCCAGCCCAAGGGUUGAUGCAGGUUUAUCACUAAAACUUGCAGAGGUUAAGGCUGUUGUGGCCGAGCGGGGUUGGCGACACAGCCUGUGGGUCCCCAGUGGGGAGGGGUCUGCAGCCUUGGCCCCCCACAGAACUUCUGAGCACAAAUCAUCCCUGGUUCCACUAGAUGCCAGGGAGCAUGAGUGGAUUGUGAAGCUUGCCAGUGGCUCCUGGAUUCAGGUGUGGACUUUGUUCUGGGAGGACCCUCAACUGGCCUUGCACAAAGACUUUUUGACUGGGUACACUGCGUUGCACUGGAUAGCCAAACAUGGUGACCUCAGGGCCCUUCAGGACUUGGUGUCUGGAGCAAAGAAGGCAGGGAUUGUCCUUGAUGUAAACGUGAGGUCCAGUUGUGGAUAUACCCCGCUGCACCUUGCAGCCAUUCACGGCCACCAGGGGGUCAUCAAAUUGCUAGUGCAAAGGUUGGCUUCUCGGGUAAAUGUCAGGGACAGCAGUGGGAAGAAGCCAUGGCAGUAUCUAACCAGUAAUACCUCUGGGGAAAUAUGGCAGCUGUUGGGAGCUCCUCGGGGCAAGCCCAUUUUCCCUGUCUAUCCCUUAGUUGGAAGUUCUUCCCCUACCAGAAAGGCCAAGAGCAAGGAAAUAUCUAGAAGUGUCACCCGAAAAACUUCCUUCGCUGCACUACUCAAAAGUCAGCACAACAAGUGGAAACUGGCCAACCAGUAUGAGAAAUUCCACAGUCCAAGGGAAAGAGAAGAGUAUAGUGACUGAGGUGGGUCUCUCUGUCCAACAUGCAGGCAGCACUCCCUCAUCCUGCUCAGUGAGAGAAUUCAGGGGGAAUAGAAAAGCUGCUGAGAGUUGGUAAAGAGGAUGGUCGAGUGAGAUGGUGUUGACCUCCCUGGAUCUUAUGUCACUACAUCCUGGACCUCAAGAGGGUCAUCCAAGCUUUUUGAAAGCUGAACUCCUUGACUGGAGAAACCUAGACAAGAGGCGGGGCCAGGUGCUUGAUAUCUAGGAGGCAUUCUUCCUCUUCCCUUGCCACCAUGGAGCUGGGCACAGUAAGCCAUAUUGUUUCCUGAAGCAGGAGUCCCAGGCCUUGGCUAGAGAGGGAACAGAUGUCUAACAAAAAGAGAAGCAAUUCGAGGAAUUGAUGAAGCACAAUUAAAAUCCUCUCUGGCUAGUAGCUCUCUGGCUUCUGUUCAUUUGAAGAAUAAAUCUUGGCUGACAGUGGGAAGCACCAGGUUUGAAAUCAGAUGGCUUUAUUUUUCUUUUUUUGGCAUUUAAAUCAGUGAAAUAAAAUUAUUACUGGAGAGCACAGUUCGAUUUAAGAGAUUCCUCAGCCCUGUUCUCAAGUCUUCUUUUGAAUUCCAUGCAUGGUGGUUAAUGGGUAAAAUGAUUAAUGCCUCCUUUGGGUCUUCUCACUGAUCAGAGAAGCAGCUGGGUAAGAUCCAGUUAUGACUUGGACUCCAUUCCUAAGAGGAAUGACUGUCAUUCAGGCCCUGCUUUUUUGUAUCAACCCGAAGGGAACUUUCCAAAUGUAAAAACCAUGUGGCUCAUUUACAUAGUGACUGAAACCAUCUUUCAUGGAAACUCCCUGUGUAACAAACAGAAUUAUCGUUACUAGUUUUCAGAGGUUUGAAUGGCCAACGUUUGUACUCAUAAAAAGAGAGAAAUGAUUUCACUCUGGGGAAACAGUAAGGGUUAAGAGAAUGCAUCCUUACCAGGACUAUCUAAGCCGCUAAAUAUAAUUGUAUUUGCACUAAACUUGUUGCCAAUUAAGAUUAAAUAUUAGCCUUUAAGUACUCUAUAUCUAACAUGAAGUGCUCCUUUUUAAUUGCUUUUGAAGAGACCGAUAACUUGUGAGUUCAUGGAGUGAGAAAAUGGCUAGUCUAUAAACGUCAGUAGAGCAUCAAGAUUUCAGAAUAAGUUCAAAGAGGGCUGAAAUACAUGUUCAAGUGGAAAUUGUUAAUUUUUUAUGGGAAUGUUUUCAUGAGAUGUGACAAUGAUGCUGUAUUUUAAGUCUUUUUGUGUUUCUUCUGGUUAUUUGCCCCCAUUAAAAGAUCAAUAGAUCUUUAUAAUUUAUUAUA